AUCAAGACGGAAGUAACAGCGGAAAGGAAGUUCCAAGGCCCGCGCUGGGAAAAAGGUGGGGGGACCAGGGGAAGACUCGGAGUGCGAUGGCGGCGCAAAUUCCAAUUGUGGCCACCACUUCCACUCCCGGAAUAGUCCGGAACAGCAAGAAGAGGCCGGCCAGCCCUUCCCACAAUGGCAGCAGCGGCGGGGGCUAUGGCGCCAGUAAGAAGAAAAAAGCGUCCGCUUCCAGCUUUGCGCAGACGUGCCUUUCGCCUUCCACCAUGAUUGUGAGGCCUCCCCAGCCACGUGGAACUACGUGCCUCUUGCCUUCCGCCAUGAUUGUGAGGCCUCCCCAGCCGCGUGGAAAUGGUAUCAGCAUGGAAGCCAUGAGUGAGAAUAAAAUGGUGCCCUCUGAGUUUAGCACAGGACCUGUGGAAAAAGCUGCCAAACCUUUGCCAUUUAAGGAUCCCAACUUUGUGCACUCUGGCCACGGUGGCGCAGUAGCUGGCAAGAAGAACAGAACCUGGAAGAACCUGAAACAAAUCCUCGCUUCUGAAAGGGCAUUGCCGUGGCAACUGAACGAUCCUAACUACUUCAGUAUUGAUGCUCCUCCAUCCUUUAAGCCAGCUAAGAAGUAUUCUGAUGUUUCAGGUCUGCUUGCCAACUACACAGACCCCCAGAGCAAACUGCGGUUCAGCACCAUUGAAGAGUUUUCCUACAUUCGGAGGCUGCCCUCUGACGUCGUCACCGGCUACCUGGCCCUGAGGAAGGCCACGAGCAUCGUUCCCUGAGCCCCAGAAAGGGAGAUGAAGUGGAAAGCUGUUUCAAAAACAGACUCUGGACUCAUGAUUUUGUUUCACGGAAACAAACUCGUUCUGCUGUCAAUCUGAAAAUGCCAGUGCUGUGCCUUGGAAAGAAUGUUUGGCUUUAAUUUAAGGGUUUUUUUUUUUUUUAGUGUGUGUUUUCCCUCCAAGUGUGAUAUUUCCUGCUGAAUUAAAUUAUACUUCAGUUGUUGCCUCAAGUAAAGGUGUUUGACAAGAAGAUACAAUAAAACCAUACUUUUCAUUUA